ACUUCCCUCUGUGGCUCUGCUCAGAACUGGCGGUUUUUCCCAGCUCCUUGCCCAGACCAAUACUUCCAUGCUGUCUUCAAGCCCUGCUUCCUGCACAUCUCCCAGCCCAGAUGGGGAGAACCCAUGUAAGAAGGUCCACUGGGCUUCUGGGAGGAGAAGGACAUCAUCCACAGACUCAGAGUCCAAGUCCCACCCGGACUCCUCCAAGAUACCCAGGUCCCGGAGACCCAGCCGCCUGACAGUGAAGUAUGACCGGGGCCAGCUCCAGCGCUGGCUGGAGAUGGAGCAAUGGGUGGAUGCUCAAGUUCAGGAGCUCUUCCAGAGUCUUGCUCUGUCACCCAGGCUGGAGUGCAGUGGUGUGAUCCAUUCUCUGCAACUUCUGCCUCCCGGGUUCAAUCGAUUCUCCUGCCUCAGCUCCUGGAGUAGCUGGGAUUACGGGAUCAAGCAACCCCUUCUGAGCCUGAGAUUGACCUGGAAGCUCUCAUGGAUCUAUCCACAGAGGAGCAGAAGACUCAGCUGGAGGCCAUUCUUGGGAACUGCCCCCGCCCCACAGAGGCUUUUAUCUCUGAGCUGCUCAGUCAACUCAAGAAACUCCGGAGACUCAGCCGGCCUCAGAAAUAAGCCUGAGAGACCAUCUUUAGCAGCCUCAGCACUGCCAGGCCUGCCCUGAAACUCCAGAUCCUGGCUAAGAGGGAAAUAGCUCCUUGGGACACAAACAAGAAAUGUGGACAAGGAGGGACAUUUGCAUACUCCUACUGUCUGUGUGGUCACAGCUAGUUUCUGUCAGCUGGGCUCUCUGGGAGAAAGCUGGCUGUUGUCCAAUGCCUUCCUUGGCAGCCAAGUGGAUAAAACCUUUAGGAGCCCCA